AGCUUUAAUCAAUGCUGGCCUGAGAACAGGAGCGGAACAUUGCCUAGUAGACCCUGAGGCUUUACAACAGUGCCACUGACCCCUAUGAGCCUGAUGCUGGAUGACCAACCCCCUAUGGAGGCCCAGUAUGCAGAGGAGGGCCCAGGACCUGGGAUCUUCAGAGCAGAGCCUGGAGACCAGCAGCAUCCCAGUAGGCCAGACUGGGCCAUAGGGGAAUGACAGGGUGGGGACAGUGGAGGGCAAUCAUCCUACAUUCCCCGGAUCCUCCUUGGGGUCAGCCCCACAUGAUUGAUGUUUCUCAGGCAGUGUGCUGGCGUUCCAUGCGACGUGGCUGUGCAGUGCUGGGAGCCCUGGGGCUGCUGGCCGGUGCAGGUGUUGGCUCAUGGCUCCUAGUGCUGUAUCUGUGUCCUGCUGCCUCUCAGCCCAUUUCCGGGACCUUGCAGGAUGAGGAGAUAACUUUGAGCUGCUCAGAGGCCAGCGCUGAGGAAGCUCUGCUCCCUGCACUUCCCAAAACAGUAUCUUUCAGAAUAAACAGCGAAGACUUCUUGCUGGAAGCGCAAGUGAGGGAUCAGCCACGCUGGCUCCUGGUCUGCCAUGAGGGCUGGAGCCCCGCCCUGGGGCUGCAGAUCUGCUGGAGCCUUGGGCAUCUCAGACUCACUCACCACAAGGGAGUAAACCUCACUGACAUCAAACUCAACAGUUCCCAGGAGUUUGCUCAGCUCUCUCCUAGACUGGGAGGCUUCCUGGAGGAGGCGUGGCAGCCCAGGAACAACUGCACUUCUGGUCAAGUUGUUUCCCUCAGAUGCUCUGAGUGUGGAGCGAGGCCCCUGGCUUCCCGGAUAGUUGGUGGGCAGUCUGUGGCUCCUGGGCGCUGGCCGUGGCAGGCCAGCGUGGCCCUGGGCUUCCGGCACACGUGUGGGGGCUCUGUGCUAGCGCCACGCUGGGUGGUGACUGCUGCACAUUGUAUGCACAGUUUCAGGCUGGCCCGCCUGUCCAGCUGGCGGGUUCAUGCGGGGCUGGUCAGCCACAGUGCCGUCAGGCCCCACCAAGGGGCUCUGGUGGAGAGGAUUAUCCCACACCCCCUCUACAGUGCCCAGAAUCAUGACUACGACGUCGCCCUCCUGAGGCUCCAGACCGCUCUCAACUUCUCAGACACUGUGGGCGCUGUGUGCCUGCCGGCCAAGGAACAGCAUUUUCCGAAGGGCUCGCGGUGCUGGGUGUCUGGCUGGGGCCACACCCACCCUAGCCAUACUUACAGCUCGGAUAUGCUCCAGGACACGGUGGUGCCCUUGUUCAGCACUCAGCUCUGCAACAGCUCUUGCGUGUACAGCGGAGCCCUCACCCCCCGCAUGCUUUGCGCUGGCUACCUGGACGGAAGGGCUGAUGCAUGCCAGGGAGAUAGCGGGGGCCCCCUAGUGUGCCCAGAUGGGGACACAUGGCGCCUAGUGGGGGUGGUCAGCUGGGGGCGUGGCUGCGCAGAGCCCAAUCACCCAGGUGUCUACGCCAAGGUAGCUGAGUUUCUGGACUGGAUCCAUGACACUGCUCAGGACUCCCUCCUCUGAGUCCUGCUGUUUCCUCCAGUCUCACUGCACACCACUGCCUCAUGCUUCCUGGGGCCUCCAGCAGCUCCACUAAUGGAGGAGAGGCAGUAGCCUCCGACACAGAACGCAUGGACCUCCUACUACUGUGUGUGAGGAACAGUCACUACCCACUGGCCAGCCACCCAGCCAACAGGUCUCUCCUCUUGGGCCCUGAUUUCAGAGUCCUCUUUCUCACUAGAGACUCAAUGACAGAAGAGAGGCUGGGACUUGGUUGGGCAUGCUGUGGUUGCUGAGGGAUGAGGGGGAGGAGAGAGGUAGGAGCUGGAGAUGAAGAGGCUGCUAGAAGCAGCAGGAAGCCUGCCCUUCUGCCCUCUCCCCUCCCUGCCCCUGUGUGAGUCUUUUGGGAGGGUGCUGGGAGGUGCCCCCCGUCCCACCUUUUUCCUGUGCUCUAGGUGGGCUAAGUGCCUCCCUAGAGGACUCCAUGGCUGAGAGGCUCCUGGGCAGAUGGGGUCAAGGCUGGGCCAGCCCAGAUGAAGCCUAUGGGAGUCAGGACCCUCUCCACUCUCCCUCUCCACUCCCCUUCCUGUUCUCACCUGGCUGUGGCUGGCCCUGUGUGGGGUGGGUACACUGGAAAACAAGAAGGUUGGAGUUGGUCUAGGACAUUGGUUUUAAAUGACAGUUCUGUGAACUGGUCCAAGGAGUUCUGUUAUUAAAGUGAUAUAUGGUCUUGG